AGUCGGCGGCGGCUGCUGCUGCCUGUGGCCCGGGCGGCUGGGAGAAGCGGAGUGUUGGUGAGUGACGCGGCGGAGGUGUAGUUUGACGCGGUGUGUUACGUGGGGGAGAGAAUAAAACUCCAGCGAGAUCCGGGCCGUGAACGAAAGCAGUGACGGAGGAGCUUGUACCACCGGUAACUAAAUGACCAUGGAAUCUGGAGCCGAGAACCAGCAGAGUGGAGAUGCAGCUGUAACAGAAGCUGAAAACCAACAAAUGACAGUUCAAGCCCAGCCACAGAUUGCCACAUUAGCCCAGGUAUCUAUGCCAGCAGCUCAUGCAACAUCAUCUGCUCCCACCGUAACUCUAGUACAGCUGCCCAAUGGGCAGACAGUUCAAGUCCAUGGAGUCAUUCAGGCGGCCCAGCCAUCAGUUAUUCAGUCUCCACAAGUCCAAACAGUUCAGUCUUCCUGUAAGGACUUAAAAAGACUUUUCUCCGGAACACAGAUUUCAACUAUUGCAGAAAGUGAAGAUUCACAGGAGUCAGUGGAUAGUGUAACUGAUUCCCAAAAGCGAAGGGAAAUUCUUUCAAGGAGGCCUUCCUACAGGAAAAUUUUGAAUGACUUAUCUUCUGAUGCACCAGGAGUGCCAAGGAUUGAAGAAGAGAAGUCUGAAGAGGAGACUUCAGCACCUGCCAUCACCACUGUAACGGUGCCAACUCCAAUUUACCAAACUAGCAGUGGACAGUAUAUUGCCAUUACCCAGGGAGGAGCAAUACAGCUGGCUAACAAUGGUACCGAUGGGGUACAGGGCCUGCAAACAUUAACCAUGACCAAUGCAGCAGCCACUCAGCCGGGUACUACCAUUCUACAGUAUGCACAGACCACUGAUGGACAGCAGAUCUUAGUGCCCAGCAACCAAGUUGUUGUUCAAGCUGCCUCUGGAGACGUACAAACAUACCAGAUUCGCACAGCACCCACUAGCACUAUUGCCCCUGGAGUUGUUAUGGCAUCCUCCCCAGCACUUCCUACACAGCCUGCUGAAGAAGCAGCACGAAAGAGAGAGGUCCGUCUAAUGAAGAACAGUUCUAUAAGAUCAGAGGCCUUCAUUGGAUCUCACUGGGCUAAAAUGAAGGUGUCAGCAGGACUGCAUUCCUUCCUGGAGGUUCUAGGGAAGCAGCUCGAGAGUGUCGUAGAAAGAAGAAAGAAUAUGUGAAAUGUUUAGAAAACAGAGUGGCAGUGCUUGAAAAUCAAAACAAGACAUUGAUUGAGGAGCUAAAAGCACUUAAGGACCUUUACUGCCACAAAUCAGAUUAAUUUGGGAUUUAAAUUUUCACCUGUUAAGGUGGAAAAUGGACUGGCUUGGCCACAACCUGAAAGACAAAAUAAACAUUUUAUUUUCUAAACAUUUCUUUUUUUCUAUGCGCAAAACUGCCUGAAAGCAACUACAGAAUUUCAUUCAUUUGUGCUUUUGCAUUAAACUGUGAAUGUUCCAACACCUGCCUCCACUUCUCCCCUCAAGAAAUUUUCAACGCCAGGAAUCAUGAAGAGACUUCUGCUUUUCAACCCCCACCCUCCUCAAGAAGUAAUAAUUUGUUUACUUGUAAAUUGAUGGGAGAAAUGAGGAAAAGAAAAUCUUUUUAAAAAUGAUUUCAAGGUUUGUGCUGAGCUCCUUGAUUGCCUUAGGGACAGAAUUACCCCAGCCUCUUGAGCUGAAGUAAUGUGUGGGCCGCAUGCAUAAAGUAAGUAAGGUGCAAUGAAGAAGUGUUGAUUGCCAAAUUGACAUGUUGUCACAUUCUCAUUGUGAAUUAUGUAAAGUUGUUAAGAGACAUACCCUCUAAAAAAGAACUUUAGCAUGGUAUUGAAGGAAUUAGAAAUGAAUUUGGAGUGCUUUUUAUGUAUGUUGUCUUCUUCAAUACUGAAAAUUUGUCCUUGGUUCUUAAAAGCAUUCUGUACUAAUACAGCUCUUCCAUAGGGCAGUUGUUGCUUCUUAAUUCAGUUCUGUAUGUGUUCAACAUUUUUGAAUACAUUAAAAGAAGUAACCAACUGAACGACAAAGCAUGGUAUUUGAAUUUUAAAUUAAAGCAAAGUAAAUAAAAGUACAAAGCAUAUUUUAGUUAGUACUAAAUUCUUAGUAAAAUGCUGAUCAGUAAACCAAUCCCUUGAGUUAUAUAACAAGAUUUUUAAAUAAAUGUUAUUGUCCUCACCUUCAAAAAUAUUUAUAUUGUCACUCAUUUACGUAAAAAGAUAUUUCUAAUUUACUGUUGCCCAUUGCACUUACAUACCACCACCAAGAAAGCCUUCAAGAUGUCAAAUAAAGCAAAGUGAUAUAUAUUUGUUUAUGAAAUGUUACAUGUAGAAAAAUACUGAUUUUAAAUAUUUUCCAUAUUAACAAUUUAACAGAGAAUCUCUAGUGAAUUUUUUAAAUGAAAGAAGUUGUAAGGAUAUAAAAAGUACAGUGUUAGAUGUGCACAAGGAAAGUUAUUUUCAGACAUAUUUGAAUGACUGCUGUACUGCAAUAUUUGGAUUGUCAUUCUUACAAAACAUUUUUUUGUUCUCUUGUAAAAAGAGUAGUUAUUAGUUCUGCUUUAGCUUUCCAAUAUGCUGUAUAGCCUUUGUCAUUUUAUAAUUUUAAUUCCUGAUUAAAACAGUCUGUAUUUGUGUAUAUCAUACAUUGUUUUCAAUACCACUUUUAAUUGUUACUCAUUUUAUUCACUAAGCUCGAUAAAUCUAACAGUUACUCUUAAAAAAAAAAAAAAAAGACUAAGGUGGAUUUUAAAAAUUGGAAACUGACAUAAUGUUAGGUUAUAAUUUCUCAUUUGGAGCCGGGCGCAGUGGCUCACGCCUGUAAUCCCAGCACUUUGGGAGGCCAAGGUGGGUGGAUCACCUGUGGUCAAGAGUUCAAGACCAGCCUGGCCAUCAUGGUGAAACCCCAUCUCUACUAAAAAUACAAAAAUUAGCCAGGCGUGGUGGCUGGCGCCUGUAAUCCCAGCUACUCAGGAGGUUGAGGCAGCAGAAUUGCUUGAACCCAGGAGGCAGAGGGUUGCAGUGAGCCGAGAUAGCACCAUUGCACUCCAGCCUGGGCGACUCCAUCUCAAAAAAUAAAAAUAAAAAAAAUGUCUCAUUUGGGAAGGAAAUUCCUUUUAAAAAAGAGUUGAGACACUUAGAAAACUAAUGUUUUAUAUUUAGUCAAGAGUUAUUUAAGAAAGUCAAGCUUGUUUAACAACAAAAUAUGAAGAUUUAAGUGUUAAUUGCUGGAUCCAUUUUAAAAUAAGAUUUUAAUUAACAUUUGUAAAUGGUAUAUUUUCGUUUGUAACAAACCAUUGUCUUUUUUCAAGGAUGAACAGAGUUUAUGAAGGAGCAUCAUUCUAAGAAUUAAGUGAUGUAGUCUUUAUGUUUGGACAGUUCACCAGAUUCUCAAGAAGGCUUUCAAACAACUAUAAAGUUUGAUGUUUGUCCUGCUGAGCUAAUGGGGAAAGUUAUAGCAUAAAAAUUGUGUAACCGCAUAGAUAUGUCAUUUUUAAAAACUGGUUUAACAGAAAUCAAGCAAAGUCACAAAUAUGUUCACAAGUUGGAAUUAUUUAUUGAGUCAAAAUGUCGAAUCGAACAUUUUGAAUGAAGUAAGUGUUAUAAAUGAAAAAUUGCCUGAUGUUUAGCAGUUUGUAUUCUCUAAAGCUUUUUUUCAAAAGUUCAGGCUUUCUACUUACUGGGAAGUUGGUGGUCCUCUUAGUCCCUGAUAAAUCAAGGCAAUCACAUUCAUGUGAGCUGGAUGAAUUUAUAAGUUAUAAAGACCUUAUCCUUCAUACCUUGAGGAUGAUUGCACUGGUUUUGAAGUCAGUUGCUUAAUGAUGAGGUGAGAAAUGUAUCCUGUUGCUAAAUCUGUCUUAGACCCUUGGUGAAACUUGAAGAUUUCAGUUUAUAAAGAUAAAAUCAAGCAUCUUUUGUGCAGUUUUCUUUUUUUAAUGCAAGAAUGGUGGGGAGGUUUGUUUGUAAGCAUGAAACUUUGAGAAUCUUUAUUAAGAAAAUGACAUAAUUUUUAAAAACCUUGUAGCCAAGAACAUAUGUGGCCACAUUACCAGUAAUAAAUGUUUUUCUCUUUAUAUUGGCCAAAAGGGAAUAAAAAUGUCAUCAUAGGAAUUUGUACAUAUGCUACUGAUUUGCCUAGAAAAUAGCAAGUUUGAUAUUGCUCACUUUGCAAAUAUAGGGCCAUGUGGCACUUUUAUCUAUAGGACAGAUUAAUAAAAAUGAAGUGGGGAGGGGUUUAUUUUUGAUAUAUUACUCUUAUGAGUUUUCAAGCUUUGAUAAUGUUUAACUGAAAAGUGGCUUAGAAAGGGCUAGAUCCAAUGUGUUCAUUAUUAAAUAAUUGCUAUCAGAUACAAUUUUAAGUUCAUUCUUUUUCAAACUCAAGUACCAUAUUGGCAACCAUAAUAUUGUCAUAGGUGCUCUCUUCAUUUAGAUAUUCUUGGGGGGGGUGGCAUUUGUAUAAUAUAUGUGUACAUAUAUAUAUAUAUAUAUAUAUAUACAUACAGUAUAUAAUCUAAAGCUCUGAGAGCUCUUAAGUCAGGAAUGCUGAGUAUUAUAGUAUAUUGAGGUCAGAUGAAAUUUUACAUUUUUGUGUGUUCUGUUGCAUUCCUUCUGGUAGUUUCUAUGACUGCAUUACUCCAGCACUCAUGAUUGAUUUUAUCUUCUAAUUUUCUUCCAAGUAUUUUAUUUUUUAUUAGUUUUCUUUGGCUUGAUACUUUUAAAUAUGUUACUAGUCACUUGAAAGCCUCUCCCCCAAAAGUAUUUGGUUUGUAUGCUUUGUCUGUGGCAGCUAUAACAGUGGUAAGAACAUUUUGAAGAUAGCUUUUUAAAGGAACCACUGAUUUUUUCAAAAAUCAUCCUGGGGGAGGAAUUUUGGCAUUUCAUUUGAGCAGGGAUUUUGUCAGAAAAUGUGUUUUGAUGGUAGGUCAGCAGCAGUGCUAGUCUCUGAAAGCACAAUACCAGUCAGGCAGCCUAUCCCAUCAGAUGUCAUCUGGCUGAAGUUUAUCUCUGUCUCUCAGGAUAAAUCCCUGUAGGACAAAUCCCUACUAUCAUUUCUACCUUUUGGGGUGACAUGUGGAAUCAUACAAAGGCUUAGGAAGAAAUACGUUUGUUUAAACCAGGAUGCUUUACUUACUUGAAGUGACUUCAAUCUAGAUUUCUUUUAAUAUUUAACAAAUUUUUAAUUCUAUGAUCAGCCACAGUCAGCUAUUACCAUAAAUUGGUCUCUGUUUAUUUUGAAGAUCACGGCUGCUUCAUUUUGCAGGAUUAAGUAGGGCUAAUGUAUCUUAAAGUUAAGAUCUUGAAUUAAAGUGAGUUUUAGAAAUAGUGUUACAUACCUUUUCAGUUGUUUUCAAGAGGCUUUAUUUUUGUUGCCUUUGUAGCCCUGAAAGCUGUUGGUAUAUUUUUUCCCUCAUGGACCCAAUAGAAAAGUUGUAUAUUUAUUUGGAUUAUAUUUACAUUCUGUCCUUUGUAAAUGUUUGGUGUAACUUGCACUUUUUUAAAUGACCCAGUUUGGGUAUUAGCAACUUAAGAAAUUCCCUCAUCAAGUAAUUCUCAACUUUUUAGUCUUUCUCCUCUCUUCAAAUCAUGUGACUUUUUAAAUGGAAGUUUUUCAUUGAUUAAAAUAUUUUAGCACCUAAAAGCUAGCCUUAAAAACAGCUGUAAAAGAAAAACAUCAGGAAAUUAGAUAUGACUAGCCCAGUUAAUUAAAAGACGGGCUCAAACCUUGUUUUAUUCUUUUUCAUCUUGGAUGAAGAUUGAAGGGAAAAUAACUCAAGUGCAUAAUAUUUAUUUUCAAUUUUUAAUGAGACUUUAUCCUCAUCACAACAUUAAUACUGUACAUAGUAUGCCAAAAUAUCCAUUAAUUUGUCUAGAAUAGUACAAGACUUUUUAAAGCAAUUGUCCUCACAGAGACCACAUGUAAUAUACUGAAAUAUGUUCAUUUUUAAUGGCUUUGUUAACAUCAAAGAAAUGCUGCCUAAAUUUGAUUUCAGAUGAGGAAGGAGAAAGUAAAGUGUGCAUAGUAAGGCUGUAGGUGAAGAGUUGUGAGAUAAAUAGUUCACUCAGUUGUACAAAGCACAACUAGAACUUUUUGUUGGGAGGCUUACAUACAUCUUGAAUAUUCUUAAUGUAAUAAUGUUGACUAUUAAGUUGGCUACACAGUCACUGUAUGUACUAGGAACUGGUUUCCUUGACAUUCUAGAAUCAAUGGCUAGGAGAGGCAUUAAUCUUUGAGGGGCUGAACAUAUCAUGAAGCUGAGUCAGUAUGGAAAAUUUUCAAAUAAACAGGGUGCUGAAGUUCCAUCUGUCUCAUCUGCUUAUGAUAAGUUCUUAUUGAUUAGUGAAUGUAGCUUAAGCCUUUGUAUGUGUCCUCAGGGGGCAGACCGACUUUAAGAGGGACCAGAUAACGUUUGAAUGGAGGGAUUAUAUUUCAGGUGUUUUAGCUUGAAAUUUAUUUUUUAAAAAAAGAAAAAUUUAAAAAAUAUAUAAAUAAAAUAGAACAAAGCCGGUGAUGCAAGUUGAUAUUAUAAACAGGCAGUUUUAGCACAGAAAGAAAAUACUGACCUGUCUGCAUUCUGGUACGGUGGGUGCAGGUCCCAGCUGGGUAUGACAUGAUACAUUUUUAAUUAUUCUCACCAGCAAGUAAAAGGAAAAUGAACAAUCUUUUGGAAUUGUCUUUGAAAAGGAUCAAAGAGUAGGAAAUUCACAUUUGACCUAACAUUACUUGCCUAUAGAAGUAUGGCAUUUCCAAGCUUUUGUCUGAGGAGCAUCUCAGAGAAGUGAGAGUAAAUCUGAGUUAGCUUAAAAAUUGGUAGGGAGGAAGAAAAUCUCUGCAAAUAAUGAUUUUAUGUUUGUUGGCCAAGUGAAAUGAUCUAUCAUUGUGUUUGGGAGGUUUUAUUUUCUUAUGUUUUUAAAAUUGGUAAAUGCUUUAUAGAUGUAUUUUUAUCCAAGUGCCACUCCAAUUUGUGUAUGUAAUAAAAUUAUUUAUAUUAAAAGUGGGAAAUAAUUGUCAACAUUUUUUUUGAGUAUAGAUUUAUUAGGGGUGGCAAAGAAGAGUGCUAGUUAGCAGUUUUCCAUGUAAAGUUGUCCUUGACUGAUUUGUCCACAUGUCAGUUGUAACUCCCCCACUCCCUGCAAAAGGAAUUAUUUCUAACCCAGAUGUAUCACUUGAAACUUUUUAGAAGCAAAAUAAUCAGGGAAGUUCCUAGAAAGGUGUUUGGCUUUUUGGUUUUUGAGGGUUGGGGUAAAGAAGACUUCCCCCACAACUGUCAGCACAAAACAGGGUAUUGAUUUUUAACUCUGAUGUUUCUAUUGGAGUUGAAUACUAAAUAAAUAACUAUAAUGAGGGAAAUACAUUUCUAAUAAAAUUCCCUACAUUCUAGAAACAUCCCUGUUUUAAUUUUUUUAUCUAAAUCUUUUUGUGCUUUAUGUGUAAAGAAAAAAAUGUACUGAGUUACAAUGCAUUUUAUUAACACUAUGUACAUAAUAGCUGCUUUGUGUUCAGAAUAGUAGCAGUUGCUUUGUAUAUUAAAGUGAUCCUUGUGAAUUUGUGAAAUAUUGUCAUAAAGUGCUUUUUCUUACUGUAAUCUUUGUGGUAUCAACUGUCAUAAUGCUCUUUUUACACAAACAUUUAUGUGCAGUCACAUAAACAUGCUUUUAAAAACUCUGUAAGUCUCUUUUUUGGGGAUGGGAUCUCUAUAUUUUGUUGGGUUUUUUUUGCUAGUAGUGUGAAGCCAUGUUUUAUUGGACUUAAAGUUACAAUAUAUUACAAGCUUGUGUUGGAAGGCAGCAAAACUAAUUCAGACAACAACAUGUCUUCAGUUACUGGAUCCCUAAUUUUCAGGACAAAACCUGUUUUUCAAUAAGAUUGAACAGUGCCUAUUUGUGGAUUUGGAGAUGUUACUGUCAAGAUGACUAAUGGAGACAUACGACCAGCUGUGUCUGAUGUCAUAAAACACGUGUUCACUGAAAGGACAAUAAGACUAUAUACCUUCUCAGGUCCCCUUGCAAUUCUAAAACUCUGUGAUCAUAUAAAUUGGAAGGAAAGGGGAGGGGAUAUGGUUAAUCUUUGCUUAAGCUGUAAGAAUAAAAAAGUUAUCUCCUAUACUAUUAACUUCUGAAAUAAGUUCUGAGACGAGACAUCUGAAAAUAAGCAGCUGCAUUAUUUGUAUGUUUCUUCACUGCCAAGAUGUGUUCAAGCCUGCUAUACCUGCCAUUGUAUUGGAAGGCUUAAUGAAUUUCAUUUAUUUUCUGCAACAACGAUUACAGAAUUUAUUGCACAAAAUGAGACAUUUUGAGAGUGAUAUUAAUUACAUGAGGGACAAUAGGCAUGAACUAGGAUUGUUCUAAGCAAAUCGGAAUCGGGUCACCCUGCCACGUUCAGGUGCUUGGACCUUCAGGAAAAGAUUGCCCAUCUUGUCAUUUGACCAGGCACUGAAGUGACAAGACCAUCCUUGAGAAGUCACAUCCAAAGAUAAAAUUCUGAUCCAUUUCUAGUUUUAGUGUUUCGCCACUGAAGACUUAACAUAUGUCUUUUACACUCAGGUUGCAAAACACAGGCCCAAGACAAACUUAACUUCUCCCCCAAAUCUUCCUUCCGCUGGUUUUUCCAUCUCGUAAGUGGUGCCACUAUCCAUCUGUUAAAUUGUUUAGGGGAAACCUAGAAAAGCACUACCUUAAUCAGUGUUAUCCUUCUUCUUAACUGUGCGUCCUAAUUUCUCCACAUCUUUCUUAAGUGCAGUGACCAAACCGGAUGAGAAUUCUAACACGGGCCUGACAUCAAAUGGAAAGGAAGGAUAAUGUCCAGGAGUUGGAAUGUUAUCCUUGUUUUUAAUUAAGAUGCAAUUCACAUAAAUUAACUUUUUAAGUGAACAAUUAAGUGGUAGUACAUCCACAAUGGUGUACAACCACCACUUCUAUCUAGCUCCAAAACAUUCUCAUCACUCCAAAAGUAAAGUCCCGUUACUCUCCAUUUUCUCCUCCCACCGCCCUUGUCCCUGGCAACCACCAAUCUGCUUCCUGUUUCUUUGGAUUUACAUCCGGGUAUUUCAUGUGAGACUCAUACACUGUGUAUUACUUCUUUCGUCUAGCUUUAAUGUGUUGUUGAGGUUGAUCCAUUGUAACAUGUUAUCACUACUUCAUUCCUUUUUAUAGCUAAGUAUACUUUUUAUAGUAAGUAUGCCAUUGUAGAUAUAUACCACAAGUUUAUCGAUUCAUCCAGUUGAGUUGUUUCUACUGUUUGGCUAAUGUUCAUAGUGCUGUUAUGAAUGUUCGUGUACAAGUAUUUGAGUCCGUGUUUUCAAUUAUUUGGGGUAUAUGCCUGGGAGUGGAGUUGCUGGGUCAUGUUGAAAUCGCACAUUUAACUUUUUGAGGAACUGUCAAACUUUCCCUCAGCAGCUGUACCGUUUUACCUUCCACCAUUGAUGUAUGAGGGUUCCAAUUUCUCCACACCUUCACCAACACUUAUUUUGCCAUUUUAAAAAUUAUAGCCAUCCUCAUGGGUGUGGUCUCUCAUUGUGGUUUUGAUUUGCAUUUCCCUGAUUACUAAUGAUGUGGAGCAUCUUUUGUUGUCUUUGGCCAUCUGCGUAUCUUCUUUGAAGAAAUGUCUGUUGAGGUCCUUUGUUCAUUGAAAUUUUGUUGUUGGGUUCUGAGUUCCUUAUAUAUUCUGGGUACUAGGCCCUUAUAAUAUUUUCGCCUAUAAGUUUUUGCUUUAUAAUGUCCUCAUUGUUUUCAAACUUACUUUAUGUAAUAUGUACACUUCUAAAAAAAAGAAACAUGGAAAAGGGCAAACUGUAAGAAGUUUUUUGUGUUAUGUUUUUUGUGACAGUCUGUGCAUAUAUACACAAAUAUAAUGUAUGUUCUCUCCUCCUCCCUCUCCCUUUUUUUACACAAAAGGUAGGUACAAACAGUGGUUUAUAAACUGCUGCCAUUGUACAGAUACAGUUUAACCAGUCCUCUUCUGGGGACAUUUGGCUGUUUGAAAUUUUUUACUGUUACAGAUAUACAGAGGUUGGUAACUAGGUCUACACAAGUUGUAUCUCCAGGAUACUGAGAAGUAAAAGUUAUUUCUGAAUUAUGGUUUUCUUCAUAUUUGGAUAUUGUUUCCUAAUGAUUAUUAGGUAUCUGCUAAGCAAUUUUUAUUAACUUAUGUUGAUUACUAUUUUUAUGUCAAACUUUACAGUCUAGGCAUUUUUUUCUGGAAUUAAAAUUAGAAGUGGCACAGA